AGGCUGUGGGAGCGGAUGGAGCUGCUACAGUCAGCGCUUGGGGCUGGCCUCAGCUUGUAGACCCGAGCCCUGCAGAACAACCCCCCGUGGCGCAGGAGAGCAGAAGAAAGGGGGCCUUUAUGCCCUUUUGAGGGAAGCACACAUUCUGCAAGGCCGUGGAAACAAAGGGAGGAACUGUUUGUAGCCCUCGUCCAGACGCCCCAAACAAACAGUAAGUCAGAAGGGAACAGAGCACAGCACAGUCCCUCCCUCCGCCCCAGGCAGUAUCCACCUUGCCCCGCCCCACCUAAGGAGCCCAAGGGUAUUCUGGGAGCCCACCCCAGGACAAUGGCAGGGCAAAACCAGUGAGCAAGGCAGAAAAUUCCUGAAAUUCUCCACUGAGGCCCAGCUGUUCCUCUCCUUGAAAAGUCAAGGCUUGGUUCAAGCCAGAUAGCACCUGAGGACAGAACAUAUCAGAUGGAGAAGGAAAGGCAAGUGACUUGUCCAGAGCCACUCUGUCAAAAGGGGACUUGAGUCCUCAGGGCUGUUGACUCCAAAGCUGACAAGCAGGUGGCAUUCUUCUUCAGAGCAGGGCAAGUGUAAUUCUGGACCAAUGUGUGAUUCUGAGACCAGACCAACCAACUGAAGUUACAGAUUACGAAAAUGAUAGAACCAGAAGGUGCUAACAAAAUGUCUGUCCUGCAUGUGUGGCAUUUGACAUGAAGAAACUGAGGCCCUUGCUGGGCGCAGUGGCUCAUGCCUGUAACCCCAGCACUUUGGGAGGCCAAGGCAGGAGGAUCACUUGAGCUCAAGAGUUCAAGACCAGCCUUGGACAAGAUAGUGAAACCUUGUCUCUACCAAAAAAAUACAGAAGUUAGCCAGGCAUGGUGCAGUGUACCUGUAGUAGCAGCUACUGAGGAAGCUGAGGAGCCAAGUUACACCCUGUUUAACCCUGCCUUCAAAGGGACGACUCUGUAAGAUUCUCUGCUACUUAUUCAAGUUGACACGAUGCCCUUCACACUCCACCUGAGGUCCCGCCUUCCCUCUGCCAUAAGGAGUUUGAUUCUACAAAAGAAACCAAACAUCAGAAAUACAUCCAGCAUGGCUGGAGAGCUCCGACCAGCCAGCCUGGUGGUCCUGCCCAGGUCCCUUGCUCCAGCUUUUGAAAGAUUCUGCCAGGUCAACACUGGUCCUCUACCCCUGCUGGGCCAGAGUGAGCCAGAAAAGUGGAUGCUGCCCCCUCAAGGUGCUAUCUCAGAGACCAGGAUGGGCCAUCCCCAGUUCUGGAAAUACGAGUUCGGUGCCUGCACCGGCAGCCUGGCUUCGCUGGAGCAGUACUCGGAGCAGCUGAAGGACAUGGUGGCCUUCUUCCUGGGCUGCAGCUUCUCCCUGGAGGAGGCCUUGGAGAAAGCGGGGCUCCCCAGAAGAGACCCAGCAGGUCACAGCCAGGCGGGUGCAUACAAGACAACAGUGCCUUGUGUUACCCAUGCUGGCUUCUGCUGCCCUCUGGUGGUCACGAUGAGGCCCAUUCCCAAGGACAAGCUGGAAGGGCUGGUGCGGGCCUGCUGCUCCCUCGGAGGUGAGCAGGGGCAACCUGUUCACAUGGGCGACCCAGAACUGUUGGGAAUCAAAGAGCUUUCCAAACCUGCCUACGGGGAUGCCAUGGUGUGUCCCCCAGGGGAGGUUCCAGUGUUCUGGCCUUCUCCGCUGACCAGUCUCGGAGCUGUCAGCAGCUGUGAGACCCCACUGGCUUUUGCCAGCAUCCCAGGCUGCACAGUUAUGACUGACCUGAAGGAUGCAAAGGCUCCACCUGGUUGUCUCACCCCAGAGAGAAUUCCAGAGGUCCAUCACAUUUCCCAAGAUCCUCUGCACUACAGCAUCGCGUCAGUCUCUGCUUCUCAGAAGAUCAGAGAACUAGAGUCUAUGAUCGGCAUAGACCCAGGGAACCGGGGGAUUGGGCACCUGCUCUGUAAAGAUGAGCUGCUGAAGGCCUCUCUCUCGCUGUCCCAUGCCCGCUCAGUGCUCAUCACCACUGGGUUCCCCACACAUUUCAAUCAUGAGCCUCCAGAAGAGACAGAUGGCCCACCAGGAGCUGUUGCUCUGGUUGCCUUCCUGCAGGCCUUGGAGAAGGAGGUCGCCAUAAUCGUUGACCAGAGAGCCUGGAACUUGCACCAGAAGAUUGUUGAAGAUGCUGUUGAGCAAGGUGUUCUGAAGACGCAGAUCCCGAUAUUAACUUACCAAGGUGGAUCAGUGGAAGCUGCUCAGGCAUUCCUGUGCAAAAAUGGGGACCCGCAGACACCUAGAUUUGACCACCUGGUGGCCAUAGAGCGUGCCGGAAGAGCUGCUGAUGGCAAUUACUACAAUGCAAGGAAGAUGAACAUCAAGCACUUGGUUGACCCCAUUGACGAUCUUUUUCUUGCUGCGAAGAAGAUUCCUGGAAUCUCAUCAACUGGAGUCGGUGAUGGAGGCAACGAGCUUGGGAUGGGUAAAGUCAAGGAGGCUGUGAGGAGGCACAUACGGCACGGGGAUGUCAUCGCCUGCGACGUGGAGGCUGACUUUGCCGUCAUUGCUGGUGUUUCUAACUGGGGAGGCUAUGCCCUGGCCUGCGCACUCUACAUCCUGUACUCAUGUGCUGUCCACAGUCAGUACCUGAGGAAAGCAGUCGGACCCUCCAGGGCACCUGGAGAUCAGGCCUGGACUCAGGCCCUCCCGUCGGUCAUUAAGGAAGAAAAAAUGCUGGGCAUCUUGGUGCAGCACAAAGUCCGGAGUGGCGUCUCGGGCAUCGUGGGCAUGGAGGUGGAUGGGCUGCCCUUCCACAACACCCACGCCGAGAUGAUCCAGAAGCUGGUGGACGUCACCACGGCACAGGUGUAACCGUCCAUGUUCCGUGUGAGCAGAGUCCCUACCAACGGGCAGGUCUGCAUCCGGGGAGAAUGCAGCUGCUUCUGGCGACAAUCCUGCUAGUAAACACUGGUCUUCGGUGAGCAACGAACACUCGCCUGGCCUGGGAAACUGCAUGCCCACUUUCUGGGAGGGGUUAGUGCAGGUGCUGUGGACAAAGGACAACAUUUCUCUGGGGCUUUUUAACUUUUAUUCCUAAGACUCUAAAGGCGUUGAUUUCAACCCUCCUUCACUCUGGCUUCUUCAGGCAACCCACGUGGUCUCCUGUGAGAAUCUUCUCGACAGUUACUUAUGGGGACACUUGUGAACAAUUAACUGCCAGGCAGAGCAUGAGAACAAACAUUCCCAGGCCAUGUAGGAUAGGAUACUCCAGACUCCAGUCAUCCUCCCCCAUCCAUGGUUUCUGUUACUCAUGGUUUCAGUUACUCAUAGCCAACUGCAGACCGAAAAUACUAAAUGAAAAAUUUCAGAAAUAAACAACUCUUAAGUUUUAAAUUGUGUACUCUUCGGAAUAUCGUGAUGAAAUCUCACACCAUCCUGCUCCAUCCUACCUAGGACGUGAAUCCUCCCUUUGUCCAGGGUACCCGUGCUGUCUACACCACCCGCCUGCCAGUCACCCAGCAGGUGAUCAGAUCGACUGUCAUGGUAUUGCAGUGCUUAUAUUCAAGAACCUCUUAUGUGACUCAGUAAUGUCCUCAAAGUGCAAGAGCAGAGAUGCUGGCAAUUUGGAUAUGCCAAAAAGAGGCCAUAAAGGGCUUCCUUUAAGUGAAAA